GCCACCGACACUCGCGGGCGACCAGAGCGGCCCCGCGCCGUGACUCGCUCCUAGCGGCCCUCGCAGGAUCGGACGAGGCAUUGCAGCCGCUGUGCUAGGCGCUCGCGAGGACCGCCGUUGUGAGCAGUUCGACUUUCCGCCCAAACUGGGGGAUGCUAGACCGCGGGCACCUCUGAAUCUUAUGCCUUCAGUGAUAUAAUCCUCCGUGUCCUUCGAGUCCCUCCUGCUGCAGACAGGUCCCCUAUACUUCGGUACACACGAGCCUUUCGCGCCCACCGCAACGCAGCCUCGGGAGGCAGGACAGACCCCUGCGAGUGUAGAUUGCAGCUGCAUCCCAGCUCCCCCCUCCCUGGCACGCUCCUCCACCUACAGCUGCGCUGAGCUGCCGCAUCUGAACGCAAAGCAAACGCUGCAGUGACGGUUCCUGCGUCACCUUAACUCCAAAGUAAAUGCUAACGUUUCCCGUGUCUGUACCUUCUCUCAAUCGGCACUCUCAAAACAUCUGGCACGGUGUUCACUACCCUAAUAAGACCUCAGCUUCCCUCGGGAGGGGACAUAACAAUAUAGGAAGAGUGAACCACACACCUAUCAAGGGGCACAAGAAACUUUAAUAGUGGAGGAAAGUUUGGACUCGGAAACUCAAGAACAAUAUUUGGCAUGUCAAGGAGAAUAUCAUGAGGGAGCACUGGCAGUUGCUGGGUAAUUUGAAGACGACGGUGGAGGGUUUGGUAUCAACCAACAGCCCCAACGUCUGGUCUAAGUAUGGUGGCUUGGAGCGGCUUUGCAGGGACAUGCAGAGCAUCCUCUAUCACGGGCUUAUCCGUGACCAGGCGUGCCGCCGCCAGACGGAUUACUGGCAGUUCGUGAAAGACAUCCGGUGGCUCAGUCCCCACUCAGCCCUUCACGUGGAGAAGUUCAUCAGCGUGCACGAGAACGACCAGAGCAGUGCUGAUGGUGCCAGUGAACGUGCUGUUGCCGAGCUGUGGCUGCAGCACAGCCUGCAGUACCACUGCCUCUCAGCCCAGCUCCGGCCCCUGCUCGGGGAUAGACAGUAUAUCAGAAAAUUCUACACAGAUGCUGCCUUCCUGCUAAGUGACGCUCAUGUCACGGCCAUGCUGCAGUGCCUGGAAGCAGUGGAACAGAACAACCCCCGCCUCCUGGCUCAGAUCGAUGCGUCCAUGUUUGCCAGAAAGCACGAGAGCCCGCUCCUGGUGACAAAGAGCCAGAGCCUGACAGCCCUGCCCAGUUCCACAUACACCCCUCCAAACAGCUAUGCUCAGCAUUCCUACUUUGGGUCCUUCUCUAGCCUCCACCAAUCCGUGCCCAACAAUGGCUCAGAGAGAAGAUCUACUUCCUUUCCACUCUCUGGCCCUCCCCGGAAACCUCAAGAAAGCAGAGGGCACGUCUCACCAGCAGAGGAUCAAACCAUCCAAGCCCCCCCAGUUUCAGUCUCUGCACUAGCCAGGGAUUCCCCUUUGACCCCAAAUGAAAUGAGCUCCAGUACUCUGACCAGCCCCAUAGAGGCAUCCUGGGUCAGCAGCCAGAAUGAUUCCCCAGGUGAUGCCAGUGAGGGGCCUGAGUACCUGGCCAUUGGCAACUUGGACCCCCGAGGCCGGACUGCCAGCUGUCAGAGUCACAGCAGCAAUGCCGAGAGCAGCAGUUCCAAUUUGUUCUCCUCCAGCAGCUCCCAGAAGCCAGAUUCUGCUGCCUCUUCCUUAGGGGACCAGGAAGGAGGUGGGGAGAGCCAGCUGUCCAGUGUCCUCCGCAGGUCCAGCUUCUCAGAGGGGCAGACACUCACUGUCACCAGUGGGGCAAAGAAAAGCCACAUUCGCUCCCAUUCGGAUACCAGCAUUGCCUCCAGGGGAGCUCCAGGAGGCCCCAGGAAUAUCACCAUUAUAGUUGAAGAUCCCAUUGCAGAAUCCUGCAAUGAUAAGGCGAAGUUGAGAGGCCCUUUGCCCUACUCUGGUCAAAGCAGUGAAGUCAGCACACCCAGCUCUCUGUACAUGGAAUAUGAAGGUGGUCGGUACCUGUGCUCAGGGGAAGGCAUGUUCCGAAGACCAUCAGAAGGACAGUCCCUCAUCAGCUACCUCUCUGAGCAAGACUUCGGCAGCUGUGCCGACCUGGAAAAGGAGAAUGCCCACUUCAGCAUCUCAGAGUCCUUAAUUGCUGCCAUCGAGCUAAUGAAGUGCAACAUGAUGAGCCAGUGCCUAGAGGAGGAGGAAGUGGAAGAGGAAGACAGUGAUAGAGAGAUCCAGGAGCUGAAGCAGAAGAUCCGCCUUCGGCGCCAGCAAAUCCGCACCAAGAACCUGCUCCCCAUGUACCAGGAGGCUGAGCACGGAAGCUUUCGGGUCACCUCCAGCAGCUCCCAGUUCAGCUCACGUGAUUCGGCACAGCUCUCUGACUCUGGCUCUGCUGAUGAGGUUGAUGAAUUUGAAAUCCAAGAUGGUAGCGAAGGAUCUAACCUGACUCACAUAUCAAAGAACGGACUGUCAGUGUCACUGGCCUCGAUGUUCUCAGAUGCUGACAUCAGAAGGAACACAGCCUCAAGCAGCAAAUCCUUCGUUUCCUCCCAGUCCUUCUCCCACUGCUUCCUGCACUCCACGUCUGCUGAGGCGGUGGCCAUGGGGCUCCUGAAGCAGUUUGAGGGGAUGCAGCUUCCAGCCGCCUCGGAGCUGGAGUGGCUUGUCCCGGAGCAUGAUGCCCCUCAGAAGCUCCUGCCCAUUCCUGACUCACUGCCCAUCUCACCGGAUGACGGGCAGCACGCUGACAUCUACAAGCUGCGGAUUCGUGUUCGUGGCAACUUGGAGUGGGCCCCGCCCCGGCCUCAGAUAAUUUUUAAUGUUCAUCCAGCCCCAACGAGGAAAAUUGCCGUGGCCAAGCAGAAUUACCGCUGUGCAGGAUGUGGCAUCCGGACUGACCCUGAUUACAUCAAGCGACUGCGGUACUGUGAGUACCUGGGCAAGUACUUCUGCCAGUGCUGCCACGAGAAUGCCCAGAUGGCCAUCCCCAGCCGGGUUCUGCGCAAGUGGGACUUCAGCAAGUACUACGUCAGCAACUUCUCCAAGGACCUGCUCAUUAAGAUCUGGAAUGAUCCUCUCUUCAACGUGCAGGACAUAAACAGUGCCCUCUAUAGGAAGGUCAAGCUGCUCAAUCAAGUCCGGCUGCUGCGGGUCCAGCUGUGUCACAUGAAGAACAUGUUCAAGACUUGCCGACUGGCCAAGGAGCUUCUGGAUUCCUUUGACACAGUCCCAGGCCACCUGACAGAGGACCUCCACCUGUACUCACUGAAUGACCUGACUGCGACCAGGAAGGGGGAGCUGGGGCCCCGGCUUGCUGAGCUCACCAGGGCAGGGGCUACCCAUGUGGAGAGAUGCAUGCUCUGCCAAGCCAAAGGCUUCAUCUGUGAGUUCUGUCAGAAUGAGGAUGACAUCAUCUUUCCCUUUGAGCUCCAUAAGUGCCGGACCUGUGAAGAGUGUAAAGCGUGUUACCAUAAAGCCUGCUUCAAGUCUGGAAGCUGUCCGCGCUGCGAGCGGCUGCAGGCCCGGCGGGAGGCACUGGCCAGGCAGAGCCUGGAGUCUUACCUGUCAGACUACGAGGAGGAGCCCGCGGAAGCGCUGGCCCUGGAAGCCGCCGUCCUGGAGGCCACCUGAAGAAAGCACGUGCAGCCCUCCCUCCGGGCCGGGUCACACCUGUUGCAGAACUGAGCCACUCUUUGAAGGACUCGCCCCACCUGGGGCUUCUUUUUUUUUUUUUUUUUUUAAUUAUCAUCAUCUUUUUUUUUUUUUUUACUGACUUGUCUGACGUCUGUGUGCAGUCAGCCGUCGGCAGGUUGAUGGGUCCAGAGUCUGUGGUGACAGAUAAUUUGUAAACACCAGGUGUUUCCAUCAGAACUGACAUGCGGGUCCUUCAGUGAAGCUUCUAGUGCCUCUGUCAGUGGAAGAGACAGCAAGACCAAGUUCUUCCAGCGUCUGUGGCCUUCUCCUCUAGGUUUCACCUGCAUGUCAGGUAUCAUUUCCAAUUUUCCUUUGUUUCAGUUCUGGAGCUUCUGAGCCAGGCCUUUCUCAACCACCUCUCCUGCUGCUGAAACGGGGAUGGCGUUUUCCCUCUCCCUGUCCUGGACUGGGGUCAGACUGUGCCCCGAGGAGAAGCAGCAGAGAAUAGGACUACGUCAUGGGCAUUUCGUCCACUUAUUUGGGUAUUUUGGGGGCCACAGAACAAUCCUGACUAUCCUAGACUCCUCAGAGACCUCAGAGGCAGCUGUGAAUGUCCCUAUGUUGCCGGGAGUUCCUGUUUGAAAUAUUUGAAGCAUAGAGGAUGCCACAAGCUGACUUUCUUCAUCUACCUUGGUGAUCUUGAAGCAAAGAACAGAACUGAUGCUCAGGCCAGGCUCACCUGUAGCCUUACGCCGCAAGCAUACGUGAGGCGCCAGCUCUGUCGCUGAAGGAGCGCUUACUCAGAGGAGCGGUCGGCCCCCUCUUGGUGUUAAGGUCUCUUAGUUAACCUGGCUUUUUGGUGCAGGUGUGAUCUUUGAAGCUCAGGCAGGUCCCUGAUGCCAUCCUAAGGUGAGGACAGGAACCUCACCCACCAUCUUCUUAGCGUGUCCCUGAUGACUCUGUCCUCUGUUAGAUGGUCGUUGUGCUUCUGAGUAAAAGUACAACCCGACUCCGUUCUCUCCCCUUCCUGCAGCAGAGCUGGGUCCUUCCCUGGUGGCCGAGUCUCUCUUGCCUUAGCUUCUUUGGUCAAAGUUGGAGAAAAGCUUCCUGCUAUUAGUGCUGUUACAGAACUUGACGGUUUGUGGAUGUGAGUGUGAAUGUCCCUGUGUUCUUGGGAUAACAAGAGCCUUUAUGCCAAUUAUGCACUUAACUCUGUGUAGCCUGGUAAUGUUUAUCUGUUCAUUUGAUAAUGCUGAUUUUAGUGUGCUGCCCCCCUCCCCCCGUUAAUGUGUGUUGAUGGUGAAGUCCUUUUGAUAAUGCUGAUUUUGGUGUGCUGCCUCCCCCUUCCCCCCCGUUAAUGUGUGUGUUGACAGUGAAGUCCUUGGGUGGGGCCAUGUGUGUGUUUGUGAUGUUCCUUAAGUUGAUGCAGCUUCUAACCUCUGUGAAAACACUGGUCAGAGUGGCUUCUCCAAGAGCUGGCAGCUCUGUGAACUAAAGCCUGCAUCAUUUUUGUUCUGGGAUUGAAUUCUGCCCAUGGGCAUGUCUUCUCAUAGUUGCUUGCUGGUAGGAAAGAAAUGGGCGUGGGUGCUGCCCUGGAAGCUGAGCGGAAAGUUGCCUGUGGUUGGUGGAAGCUGAUGAGAGCUUGAGCUGGCGGUAAGAAGGAGUCUCCCAGGGAAGUGGGAGAGGCAUUAAGGUGAUGGCCAGGGCUGAGGCUCCACCAGCGUGAGAGGGAACAUGUGGGAACUGGCCCCUGCCCUUGAUUCCUCUGCCUCAAAGUUGGGAUCUGAAAGCCAUGUAGGGCUAGAAGACCCUGAGGCUGUUCUCCCUUCUGUUCAUAGUGAGACUCAAAAAGCCAAGUCCCAGAAGUUCUGAAGGGCUGUGACUAGAAGUGCCCAGGUCCUUCAGGGAGCUUUAAGAAUGACCCCACAGAACUCAAGUUUAACUAGGGGUUAGGUCCCAGAUUCAGACCCAGGAGUUUAUAAAAAUGAGCUCUACUUCCAGUUUUGGUUUAAAUUACACAUCCAGGCCAGGCACAGUGGCUCACACCUGUAAUCCCAGCACUUUGGGAGGCCAGUGCGGGCGGAUCAUGAGGUCAGGAGUUUGAGACCAGCCUGGCCAAUGUGGUGAAACCCUGUCUCUUCCAAAAAUACAAAAAUUAGCUGGGCGUGGUGGCACACGCCUGUAAUCCCAGCUACUUGGGAGGCUGAGGCAGGAGAAUCGCUUGAACCUGGGAGGCAGAGGUUGCAGUGAGCCGAGAUUGCGCCACCGCACUCCAGCCUGGGUGACAGAGUGAGACUCCGUCUCAAAAAACAAAAAGGUGACACAUCCAGCUCUUUCUCCAGGUCACUGCGCUGGAGGACAGAUGUGCCGUCUUGUCCUGCCUGUUUCACAUCAGCAUAGGAUCAAAGGAUGACAAUGCUGACAGCUUCUGAAGCCGAACUCAACAGUCUCAUAGGCUCCUCACUUGUCACUUAUUUUUCCCUAGCUCCCUCAACCGCACCCCAUCCCUUUAGAUCGUGCGUCUGUUUUAGUGACUCUGACACGAUGCCGUCCUCACCUUCCAAAUACCCAGUUAUUUAUUCAAGAGGGGGGAAGUGGGUAGAGGAUGGGAUGUUUUGGAAGCACUUUGCAAGUUACCACUAUCUGAAAAUCCCCUGCUGUUGCGGGGAGAAGCUUUGAAUGCACUGAAGAGAAUUCCUUCUAAAUGAAGGCAGGUGAUAGUGUUCUUUCUGUAAGUAAAGGGAAAGAAAAAAAACAUAGUUUGCUUACCAGGUGGAGACAAGAUUCAAGACAUAGCAGAAGAGUGGAAGACAAAUAUUUUCCACUUAAAUGAGGCUGUUUUUGACGUUCUCUGCCAAGGAUUUAGAGCUUUCGUUGAACUAACAUAAAAGGAGUGCGAGUCUUAGUAGAGAUGUUCCGUGUGUGCCGCCCGUGCUCUGAACUGCGUUUCCACCUGCUGUGGUGCUUGUGCAGCCUGGCAGUUCAUUGUCAUCUUUAAUAAACUAAGGAAAUAAAAUUCUGUCUUUCGUCAGCCUGCCUUGACUGUCAAGAAAUGGCAUGUGUCCACUGUAAAGCAGGUAUAUCUGAACAUUGAGAAGGUUUCUGUGUUAUAAUGUAAAGCAAACUGGACCACACACAUCAAGGAAAGUGAGGUGGAGUGGCUGUGUCUCUAACUUGCCAUGAGACCUCGAGCGAACCACUUCACUUCUCUGGGUUUCUGGUGCAUGGUGUAACUGUCACUUAAAAUGAGGUGUCUUCCUCUCCGCAACAUCUGACUUGCCUUAGAUGCUUCAGUUCCCACUUCUGUGAGCAGCUAGCAUCUUUCUCUUCUGCUCCUGGCCCACUGGAGCUCCAGCUCUACGCUGCAACUCUCUCAACAUUUCCCCUUAAAUGUCCCCUUGUCAUCUCCAACCAGUGUGUCUAAAACCAGCAUAAAUUCCGUAUUUCCAAAAACCUAACCAUUAGUCACCCAGGUUUGAAAAUUAAUUGUCUUCAACUUCCUCUGUAAGUGGCACACUGAGCUCAUCACGCAUCGUCUCAUUCCUACUCCCUGUCAUCAAGUUCUGUGGAUGUUUUCCUCUAAAAUAAAUCUCUCAUUACUUUUCUGCCACUAGCACACAAAUUCAGGUGUUCUUGAUCAUACAUUAUUUUCCUCCCUGCGCCUCAGUGGAACAAUGAUUAGAAGCACCUUGUGGGAUGAGGAGCCGGGCGCGGUGGCUCACGAGUGUCAUCCAGUACUUUGAGAGACCAAGGCAGGGGGAUCACCUGAGGUCAGGAAUUCAAGACCAGCCUGGCUAACAUCACAAAACCUCAUCUCUACAAAAAUAUAAAAAUUAGCCAGGCAUGGUGGCAUGUGCUUGUAAUCCCAGCUACUCGGGAGGCUGAAUCAUGAGAAUCACUUGAACCUGGAAGGCGAGGGCUGCAGUGAGCCAAGCUUGCUCCAUUGCACUCCAUCCUGGAUGAAGAGCGAGACCCUGUCUCAAAAAAACAAAACAAAACAAAAAAAGCACCAGCACACUGUGGCAUGAGGGGCGGGAUUGUGACCACCUCUACCUCCCCUCUUAGUGCUCACCAAGUCUCUGCAGUAGUGAGCGUGUCCUCAUCUCCUGUCUUCUCCCUCAGCUACUUUGUCUGCAACUGCUCCUGUUGUGUUUGUCCAGCAGUCAUCAUCAGAGGACACACAUCCCAAAUGUCCUUCAGUCACUUUAUUAUUAAACUGCCAGCUCUUUCCUUGCCAGGGACUAAACCAGGAGAUAAGAUGAUAUUUAUAUGCUGUAAACACACCCUACAUAUUUAAAAAUCUUCAUAUUUACAAAUUAAACUGAGAGGAGAAUGAAAAAGCCAUGUGAAAGACUGCUGAAGUUGAUAAAAUGUUCAAAUGUUUUUCAACUAGAGAUAGGAAAAUAGCUUACAGUACAAAACCUUCACUUUGUUCUAAGGCCCUUUUGUUCAUUGUUACAAACUGGUGUAGUUCACAGGAAGCCAAAGCUUGAUUUCCAGUAAGUUCCCAAACUUCUGUUCUCAACAUUUAACUUAGAUUUUAGAUGAUCAUAUUCCAAAAUUGGAAAGACUGUUGAAGAGGAAAACAAGGACCAUUGAUUCACAAUGGCAGCCCAGCAUUUAUUUAUUCAUUCAAUCAUCCGUCAAUCCCAAACAUCUAUAGAUGCCUCCGUGUUCCAGACACCAUGCCAGAGCUGAGAGUACAAAGAAUCACAGAAUAUUGUUUAAAGAUGUUUACUGCAGCAUAAUUUAUGAAAGUAAAAAGUUAAUGGAAAAUAAAAAAAUUGAUGCAACCAUCAAAAUGACAGUUAUAAAAAUUAUGAUAGUGAGCCGCACACAGUGGCUCACGCCUGUAAUCCCAGCACUUUGGGAGGCCGAGGCGGGCGGAUCACGAGGUCAAGAGAUUGGGACCAUCCUGGCCAACAUGGUGAAACCUUGUCUCUACUAAAAAUACAAAAGCUAGUUGGGCAUGAUGGCGGGCGCCUGUAAUCCCAGCUACUCGCGAGGUUGAGACAGGAGAAUUGCUUGAACCCGGGUGGCGGAGGUUGCAGUGAGCCGAGAUCACGCCACUGCACUCCACCCUGGGCAACAGAGUGGGACUCUGUCUCAAACAAAAAAAUAAAUUAUGAUAGUAACAUGGGGAAAAAGUCUUGUAAUACAAUGUUAUGUGAGAAGAAGUUAGAAAAAGUGUAUGUCAAAUAUAUAUUUAUUAGUCCAUACAUACAUAAAUAAAUGACCAAAUAAAUAAAUUCUCACAGAAGAAUUCUAAACAAAAUACGUAAAUUCUCCCAGGAGGUGGAGUUUAAUUCCUUCUCCCAUUGAGGGUGGACUGGAAUUAGUGAUUCACUUUUUUAAAUAAAAGGAUAUAGAAAGAGGAAAAUAGCAACUUUAGAGUAGAGAGAGCUAACACGACCUUAACCAAGUAAUCAACGUUAACAUCUCCAAAGAUGUCAUUGGAUGUCAUGUACCUACUAAUACAAUGAAAGGGGUACAUCUUCCCUGACAUUCAUUCAGAAACCCAUAACCUCAGUCUAAUCAUGAGAAAAACAACAAACAACAUAAACACAGGAGCAAAAUUCGAGGAACUUUCUACAAAACACUUGACCCUACUCAAAAUUGCCAAGGUCUCGAAAACAAGGAAAGAGAUGCCGUCACGGACGAGAGGAGACUAAGCAGAUACGAUGACUGAAUGCCAUGUGGGAUCCCGGGUGGGAUCCCGAAAUGGAGAAAGGAUAUUAGUGAAAAAACUGGCAAAAUCUGAAUACAAUUUGGAGUUUAGUUAAAAGUAACAUACCAAUGUUGGUUCCUUAGUUUUGGGAAAUGUCCAGUACUACAGUAAUGUAAGAUGGUAACAUUAGGGAGAGCUGAAAUCGGGUGAGGGCUAUGUGACGAAUUUGUACUAUCUUUGCAACUUUACUGUGGAUCUAAAAUUAUUCCAGAUUAAGAAGUUUACCUAUAUAAAAAGCAUAUGUACAUCAUAAUUACAGUUAUGCAAAAAUAUGGUUAGAAAAAAUACAUAAGGAAAACAUACGUAAAAAUUAGUGUGGUUCUGUUAGAAUGGUGGCAUUGUGGAGUAUUUUUUCCUCUUAUCUGCUUACUGAAUUAGCUGUAAAUGAGUCAUUUUCCAUAAAUUAAAGAGUUAAUUUUA